GCGUCCGCGCCAUCAGGCCCGAGAUAGCGGCGAGGUCCGCUUUCAGUGUAUGGUUUUCCCUGCCAAACGGUUCUGCUUGGUGCCAUCCAUGGAGGGCGUGCGCUGGGCCUUUUCCUGCGGCACUUGGCUGCCGAGCCGAGCCGAAUGGCUGCUGGCAGUGCGAUCGAUUCAGCCCGAGGAGAAGGAGCGCAUUGGCCAGUUCGUCUUUGCCCGGGACGCUAAGGCAGCCAUGGCUGGUCGUCUGAUGAUAAGGAAAUUAGUUGCAGAGAAAUUGAAUAUCCCUUGGAAUCAUAUUCGUUUGCAAAGAACUGCAAAAGGAAAACCAGUUCUUGCAAAGGACUCAUCGAAUCCUUACCCGAAUUUCAACUUUAACAUCUCUCAUCAAGGAGACUAUGCAGUGCUUGCUGCUGAACCUGAGCUGCAAGUUGGAAUUGAUAUAAUGAAGACUAGUUUUCCAGGUCGUGGUUCAAUUCCAGAAUUCUUUCAUAUUAUGAAAAGAAAGUUUACCAACAAAGAAUGGGAAACAAUCAGAAGCUUUAAGGAUGAGUGGACUCAGCUGGAUAUGUUUUAUAGGAAUUGGGCACUUAAGGAAAGCUUCAUAAAAGCCAUUGGUGUUGGACUAGGAUUUGAAUUGCAGCGGCUUGAAUUUGAUCUAUCUCCAUUAAACUUGGAUAUAGGCCAAGUUUAUAAAGAAACACGUUUAUUCCUGGAUGGAGAGGAAGAAAAAGAAUGGGCAUUUGAGGAAAGCAAAAUAGAUGAGCACCAUUUUGUUGCAGUUGCUCUUAGGAAACCCGAUGGAUCUAGACAUCAGGAUGUUCCAUCUCAGGAUGAUUCCAAACCAACCCAGAGGCAAUUUACUAUUCUCAACUUUAAUGAUUUAAUGUCAUCUGCCGUUCCCAUGACACCUGAAGAUCCUUCAUUUUGGGACUGUUUUUGCUUCACAGAAGAAAUUCCAAUACGAAAUGGUACAAAGUCAUGAUGAUUCCCUGAGUAACAAAGGGAAAUGAAAACUGUUUGUGAUCUUCCGUAUUCACUGAAAAAUAAAUGCUUGUUUAGUAUCAAAUUUUAUUUCACGAAAGUUUUUUUAAAGAACAGAAACUUUUCCAAUUAAAAAAAAAAAGCAGACUUCUGGUUCAAGAUAGCUCACUGGAAUACAUGUUUACCUCUUUCUUUCCUAAAUUGCAUUGAAUUGAUAGGAAGGAUGGCGGAAUCUUAAAGUGAUACAUGCUAACUGUAGAAAAAAAUAGAAAAUGCACAUAAGCAAAAGGAAACAUUUAAAUGCUAUCUUUCAAAGAUAACUACUCUUAAAACCUUGAGUAUCUUUUCAGACCUUUUUCUUGGCAAAUGAAUCCAUAUUGACAUAUUUGAUUUUUUUAAAAACAUGGAAACGUACUGUUUUGUAAAUUCUUUUUAACUGCACAUCUACUGUUCAUAAAUAUACCUCUGUAACAUAACUUUUUGUGGUUCUAAUGUACUCUGUUGUAUAGCUAAUACAAGUUAGGAUGCUUUUGGCCAGAGGUAACAGUGUCCAAAUAUAAUUGGCCUAAGUAACCUAGGAAAUUGUUUGACAUAACACAGGGUUCAGGGGUGUCAUUAAAGACACACUUUUUUUGCCUUGACCUCAGUUGGUUUGUUUUGCCUUAGGCUAUUCCACCUCUCGAUCACAAGAGCUGCUGCUAUAACUUCCAGUUUUACAUCUUUGUAAAAUUGUAUCUCAAAGGCAGAAAAGGCCAUUUCGUCUCUCAUUUGUUUUAUCCAUGAGGAAGAUUUUUAACAAAAGCCUCCAGAAGAUUUCCCCUCAGUUUCCAUUGACUUAGAUCAGGUUACAGAGAAAGGCAAUGUCUGACAUUUUUGGUCUCUGUUAGAAGUAGACUCUGUUGAAAAGAAAGAAGCUAAGCUAGGUGUGAAGAAUGGAAUUGGAAGCCCACUGCCUUCCCAUAAGAAAGGUUUACCAUAAUUUACUCACUUUUUUCUGUGUUAGACAUUUUGAUUAUCUGCAGUUUAUUACUACAAGCAGUGGCAGAGUGAAUGUCCUUGUACAUUUUGAGUUACAUGCUUAAUUAUGUCCUUGAGAAAGUUUCUAAAAGUGGAAUGAUUGGUUUGACUGGUUCAUAGGGCUUUAAUUAUACAAUUUACCCCUCUAAUUAGUACUAUAUGUAUGUGACUUCCCUCCCCCUGCCAGAAUACUCCUUGGUCAAUUGUAGGUAUUCUUUUUGGUUUAAUUUUUGCCAAUGUAAUUAAAAAAUGGUAUGUCAUUUUUAAAAUUUGUAUUUCUUUCAUUACAAAUAAGAUUGUUAUGUCAGUAUUGUUAUUGGCUUUUCGUAUUCCUCUUAACGUGAACCGUCUGUUCAUUGUUUUUACCUGUUUUCGUUUUAGCAAGUAGUACUUAAUUUAAAGUGUGAACUUAAUAUAUAAGAUGCCAGGACCAUCAUAUUGAUGACAAAAAUCUAUUAUGUGGUUGUAGUGCAUGUCUUGGAGUUAAACUCUUAAGUAUCAAGAAGUAAAAUAAUUUCAUUGUUUCUGUUACUAACAUUAAAAGUGUGCAAAUUGUAUAAAAUUAGGUACUUCGAUUAGUAAAAGAAAAAAAUUUGAAUGUUUUUUUUUUUUAUUUUAUUAAGCAUGCCCAGUUAUGCCAAGCAUAGUAAAUAAAGGUCAAGUAGCAUUUAUAAUAGAGGAAGUAUUGUUAUCCCUAGCAUGAGUGUAAUGGUGAUAUGAAAAACUUUGUCUUGUCAUUAUAAUAAUAAAAAAAUGAACAUUUAUUAUGGAA